ACAGUCUGCAGUCUACGGCGAGGCACAGGCCAGCCCAGCUCCACGAGGACUGAACAAGGUGCUGUCUCACUGCCACCAUGCCGGAAGUCGAGAGAAAACCCAAGAUCACUGCCUCCCGCAAACUCUUGCUGAAGAGCCUGAUGCUGGCCAAGGCCAAGGAAUGCUGGGAGCAGGAGCACGAGGAGCGCGAGGCUGAGAAGGUGCGCUACCUGGCAGAGCGCAUCCCCACGCUGCAGACCCGUGGCCUGUCCCUCAGUGCCCUGCAGGACCUGUGCCGGGAGCUGCACGCCAAGGUGGAGGUGGUGGAUGAGGAGCGAUACGACAUUGAGGCCAAAUGCCUCCACAACACCAGGGAGAUUAAGGACCUGAAGCUGAAGGUGAUGGACCUCCGUGGGAAGUUCAAGCGCCCGCCCCUGCGUCGAGUCCGUGUCUCGGCUGACGCCAUGCUCCGGGCCCUGCUGGGCUCCAAGCACAAGGUGUCCAUGGAUCUGCGGGCCAACCUCAAGUCUGUGAAGAAGGAAGACACAGAGAAGGAGCGGCCUGUGGAGGUGGGUGACUGGAGGAAGAACGUGGAGGCCAUGUCUGGCAUGGAAGGCCGGAAGAAGAUGUUUGAUGCCGCCAAGUCUCCGACCUCACAAUAGAGGCCAGCUUGCUGUGCUGCGCUCUGAGCUCCUGCUUCAUGCUUCUUCUCCAACCCAGCUCACUCACCUCUCUGCCUGUGUCUGGAGCAUCCCUUCCCACCUCUCCCCCACUUCUUCCCUCCAGCCUGCAUGCCCUCCUCUGGAACUGGGAUUAAACAGAUACCCAAGAGGCAGGAAAAACGCGAGUGUCUGAAGACCUCACCCUGGCAGGGUGGGCUUCUAUCCACCCAUGAGGCACCUGGGGCUUCUCAGCCACCCCGUGGUGUAACAAGUGGAGGAGGAGGAGGGGGUGAGAACACCUUUCCUCCAGCCCUGUGCCACACUCCUUCUAUGUGUGUACAGUGUCCACAGGCAUCACACCUUCUUCAUUAAAAACCCAGUUUCCUGGUCAUUUCUGCAGCUCUGACUGUGAGCCCUGAGAAGAAAGGGAAGACUUGGGGCUUGGGAAGAGAGGGCUGUGCUGGGCUCCAGUCACCCUGUCUGCAGUCCGGAGCUCGGGAUCUGAAGGGAGGGCUAAGGAAUUGGUGGCUGCUUGCCAGGGUCCCCUGGGGCCCCUUCUGCCCAGUCCCUGUGACGUCACACUGCACACACUCACCACCCAGGAUGCUCAGCUCACCAGAGCCCUGACCUCCGAGAAAUGACCCCGUCCUGCCCCUGACUCUGGCCAUCAGAAGAGGCCUCUCCAUUAAGAGCCGCUUCUCCUGCCGGCUUUCAUACUCUCCUUCCUCUGCAAACCUGGAUUAACUCUCCCUGAUGUGUGCUGGGUUGAGAGGUCAGGGCACUUUCAAUCCCUCACCUAGUCCUGCUGCACAGGGCAGGAGGCCUCACAGAAGAGAUACUUGCAGUUCCAGGCCUGGCCACCAGGUGACGCCUUCCUUCUCUCCUGGGCUCUCCUGUCCCUCCGGCCUCUGCUCUCCCCACGUUCACCCACCCUCCUCCCAAUUGUUUCCCCUUCACACUCCUGCACUGGUCCUAUCCCCCAGGACUGAUUCUUUCCCGGAGAUGGGGUGGCCACUUAUCUGUCCUCUGGAUCAGGUCCUUUCUCCAUCCCACUACCUCCUGGGUCCAAAGCCUGGUGAGAGCAUAGGGCCUUCUGGGGUGGAAGGGGGGUCUGGGGCAGCCUCUCUUCCCCCAACAUACUCACUAGAGUGGCUCCUGUGAAGCAGAGACCAAAGUUCUGACUUUUCUUUUUCCUUUUUUUUUUUUUUUUGAGAUGGAGUCUCGCUGUGUCACCCAGGCUGGAGUGCAGUGACGCGAUCUCGACUCACUGCAACCUCCGCCUCCCAGGUUCAAGCGAUUCUCCUGCUUCAACCUCCUGAGUAGCUGGGAUUACAGGUGCGUGCCACCACACCCCGCUAAUUUUUGUAUUUUUAGUAGAGACAGGGUUUCACCAUGUUGGUCAGGCUGGUCUCGAACUCCUGACCUCGUAAUCUGCCCACCUCGGCCUCCCAAAGUUCUGGGAUUACAGGUGUGAGCGACCACAUCCGGUCAAGUUCUGACUUUUCAGGGCAGUGGGAUGGUGACUUCUGAGCUAAGCCUGCAAGGGAAGUGGCUGUUCCCAGACCUGGGGUCCCUUGGCUUUUCGACCACCCUAGCACUGGCCCUAGGAGGGGCUGAGUUAUCAGAGCAGCAACCCUUCUACCCACCCUACUGAGUCCCCAUUCUACCUUCGAAUCCCAUGUAUUAUCUUCCAUAAGUGCCAGAAAUUGGUACAAAGUGCAGUGCCAGCUGCUCCCCAGGGCAUGGUCUGGCUCUCUGGGCUGCUGGGCUGCCAGCCCCUUUCAGAAAGCAUGGCAGUGGGAACCAGCAACUUGGGCUACCUUAGGGGAAGCAGCACUCUGCCCAGGGUUCUUGCUAUAAAUAGGUCAGUGGGCAGAGAGGCAGAUGUGUGCAAAAAGCACAACCCCAAUCACACACAGAAACCCGUAGGCACGGACACACCCAGUCUCAAUGCACGAAGUUGGAGAACCUGACAGGGCUGGUCCAGGCCACAGAGGAUGGGGUUAGGCUUCAUGCCUUCAUGCCCAGGCAGCCACAGAAACCCACUCUUCCCCGCCUCACAGGGCUCCUCCGGUUGGCCUGGAUCCAAAGCGAUCUCCUUGUUUCACCUCUUUCCAGCUCUUCCCUAGAGCCUGGCCCCAAGUUCCAGAGUCAAAUCCCAGUUUUGCAGUCAACUAUUAACCUGGGGCCCUGGCAGAUUGGGGUAUCCACCCAGUCAUGUAAAGGCAGGAGACCUGCUCUGGGCCUGACUCAAAGCAAACACGUGGGUGCAGAAGACCCAUGGGAGGAGGAGGUGGGGCCCACUCAACACACCUAAGCCAGUGGCCCUCUAGGAGGGGCAGAAGAGCCAACCAGAGGGUUCCUGGAGGUCAUCGGGUUCCUCCUUCUGCUUCCAGGCAGCAACAGACCUAAUUCAUCUCCUGUGAGGAUGGAGCAAGGGCGAAUAUAGGCAUAGACAUAUCUGGAGCGCAAGGAUUGAGAGGCCCUGUGGACAAGGGGAAGGAGAGCUUGGGGGUGGGAGAGGGAUCUAUGGAAGGGGCUGUUGUAGCCAAGAAUGGGGCCUGGGCUGGGGGCCUGGCCUCUGGAGAGCCCUGAUUCUACUCCAGUCUUCUCUCACCAUGGAGACAACACCAGUAGAGCUGGGAGCUGGGGCCUGCCACUGAGUAACAGCUCACACAUGUAGCACACUUAUGCGUCAGGCACCAGCAUGUACACCUUAAUUUAUUUAACUUUCACAACAACCCUAGGAGAAAGGUACAGCUACUAUUCUCAUGGUACAGUGGGGAAAACUGAGGCACAGAGAGGUUAGGGACUUUUCAUGAUCACACAGCUAAUAAGUGGUGGUCCCAGGAUUCAACCCAAGAAGUCUGUUAGAAUCCAUACUCUUAUCGACUAUUUUAAUAACAGCAUUUCAAUAAUAGUAAUAUGUGAUGUUAAAUGCUUUAUCUGAGUUAUAUCAUUGCAUUCUCACAAAAAUGGUACAUUUGUUAGCUCAAAUUUACAGAUGAGGAAAUGGAGGCCUGGAGAGUUCAAGUAGCUCACUCUAAGUUACAGGGUUUGCUAGCUGCAGACUGGAGACUAGAUCUCAGGUCACUCUGCCUUGGGGUUGCCCUUUUCUGAGAUCAGACUGGCCUUAACAGAGCCCAACUUUCUUGGAAGGACACAGCUGGGGGUCGAGGGUCCUGCAUAUGCACCUGGGGAGUCCCCACACACCCGCACCAAAGGGGAAACAUUCAAAGGAGAUGCAGGUGACAUACAGAUGGGCUAAGGUGAGGCCUUCCUCCAACAUGGGGCCCUGGCUGAGAGUGGAGGGAUAGGGUGCUACUUGGGGGAUAUCUAUUACUAAUCAGCACACAAUAGCUGGGUGGGCACCCCCUCUCUCUGCAGCUGGUGGAGAUGGGCCUGGUGCUCCUCUCUGCUUGGUAGGAAUGACCAGGGCAGGAUGCCACCUGCUACACUCUUGCCUGUCCCAGAGCCCUUGGGAGACCAGCUGUUGCUCCCACCUUUCCCCACAGGGUGCCCGGUCCCCACGGCGCAAGGAGGCCAAGCUCAGCUGUGUGUCUGAGCCCACUCAGCAGCAGGCAUGAUCAGGGCAGGGCCCAGCGCUAAGGGCUGCUGGGGCUAAAGUGCCUUGCUGAAGGAGGGGCAGAGUUAAACAUUAGCCACAAUGGCCCCCCGCGAAGUGAGUCAUACUCCCCACAAGUCUCUGGGCUGGGCAGCCGGGGGCGGGGGGGUUAGCUUCGUUCCAGGUGGGUGACCAAGCUGCGGAAGCCCAGGACAGUUCGCUGGGACCAGUGCUAAUGGCAGCUUCUGCUCCUGACCCCCAUCAGGUCUCUUUCCUCAGACAUCCCCAAAGCUUGUCUGCCUGUGGGUCUUUCAUUAAAGGUGACGGGCAAGGGUUUUCUCUUCCUUCCAAGACACACUUCUAGGCUGGCUUGUGGGUCCCCUGAGACGAAGGCUGAGCAGGGUGAGCCUCGAAAACCCCAUAGCACUGGCCCAGAGCACUGCGGUCAAUGUCCGAAGGACCAGAGAGGGAGGGUGACUUGCUCAAGGUCACAAACCUAACUGGAGCUAGGAAGUAGGUCCCCAGACUCCCAGUCUGAGGAAAUUGGAUGUGGACAGGGCUUUGGUCUCCUGGCCAGAGGCAAACGCCCAGGGAUCUGAACAGGCUGCCCAUCUCUGGCCUCAACUCAGCACCCCAACUGGCUCCAGUGCCAACCAUUGGCCUCUCUCACUGGUUGGCACAGGCUGGGUGAGCCUGGCCCUUUGCCCUGGGUUCAGGAGAGAGGUAUGGCUUUGCCUGGCAGUCAGGGGAGGUGUUCCAACCUGGGAGCCCCUGGGGGAGGAGCGUGUGUGUGAACGCUUGUGCCUGUUCAUCAGAAGGGGUGAGCAUGGUGUGUAUGCGUGGGCAUGCAGAAUGCAGGGUGAUGACCUGUCUGCCCGCCCUGAGUGUCACAGACACCUGUGUGUCCCCUGUACUAGUGCCUCCCAGAUGCUCUUCUCCUGACUGGCUCUUUGUGACCUAAAUUUCAACUGCUCCACCCCACAAGGAGGAAACCAGGGCCACAAAUGUAGUGAGAUUUUCAUAAAGCUAAAUGUAUUCAGUGGAAACGACCUUCCUCUGAUCUAAAAGCAUGCAUGCCUUUGUUUUAUUACUGGAGUAUUAAAUUAGCCCUUACUUAUGGAAUAGGAGGACAGUAGGUGGCAAUUGUUUUCUAAUGCUCUUACUUCACAAAAUAAAAUGGUGGCAGCACAAUGUCAGUAUUUAUAUUACACAAUAUUAUUAGUUUGUAAAAACCGAAAGCCAGGGAGCUUACUGCCCUGGAUUCUUUAGGGCGUGGGUCUUAUCACCUCAUUCAUUUCUUCCCUUCCCCUAAGAGUGCCACAAGCAUGGCAGUUGCUCAGCUGAGACACAUGAAUGGGAACAGAACUGAAAUAUCAGGAUGUGACCUCGAGCCAGCUGGUUGGGGCUGGGGAUCCCCCUGGAUCUCCACUCUGUCCUGUCCGAGAAAGGGGAAGCUGCCCUAUGAGUCUUUUUUCUGGGGGAUUCCAGAGGUUGAACGUCUGUUCUGAGGCUCCUCAGAACCUCGAGGGAGGGGACGAGAGAGAUGACCCCUUGCCCAACCACUGGCUGAAAAAUCUUGAAAUUCCCUGACUUUGACCAGGGAAUUCCCAGUUGUGCUAAGCCCUGCCUGGUGGAAUGUCCCUGGAGGAAGUAACCAGGACACGCAUACGUUUUUAAUGUACGUAUAAAGAAUCGUAAAGUGAACACCCAUCUGCCAACCACUCAUUUUAAGAACUAGGAUAUGGCACAUACUUUUGAAGCCCUUAUGCGUCCCUCCCCAAUCACAACCCCUUCCUCUCCACAAAGGUAAAUACAAUCCUCAAUUUUGUGUUUGUUAUUCUCUUGGUUCUCUUCAUAAUGUUACUACGUAUUUAUGAAUUCCUAAUACAUCAUUCAGUUUUGGA